ACAUCCGGUGUGGUCGACGGGUCCUCCAAGAGUUUGGGGCGCGGACCGGAGUACCUUGCGUGCAGUUAUGUCGGCGUCGGUAGUGUCUGUCAUUUCGCGGUUCUUAGAAGAGUACUUGAGCUCCACUCCGCAGCGUCUGAAGUUGCUGGACGCGUACCUGCUGUAUAUACUGCUGACCGGGGCGCUGCAGUUCGGUUACUGUCUCCUCGUGGGGACCUUCCCCUUCAACUCUUUUCUCUCGGGCUUCAUCUCUUGUGUGGGGAGUUUCAUCCUAGCGGUUUGCCUGAGAAUACAGAUCAACCCACAGAACAAAGCGGAUUUCCAAGGCAUCUCCCCAGAGCGAGCCUUUGCUGAUUUUCUCUUUGCCAGCACCAUCCUGCACCUUGUUGUCAUGAACUUUGUUGGCUGAAUCAUUCUCAUUUACUUAAUUGAGGAGUAGGAGACUAAAAGAAUGUUCACUCUUUGAAUUUCCUGGAUAAGAGUUCUGGAGAUGGCAGCUUAUUGGACACAUGGAUUUUCUUCAGAUUUGCACUUACUGCUAGCUCUGCUUUUUAUGCAGGAGAAAAGCCCAGAGUUCACUGUGUGUCAGAACAACUUUCUAACAAACAUUUAUUAAUCCAGCCUCUGCCUUUCAUUAAAUGUAACCUUUUGCCUUCCAAAUUAAAGAACUCCAUGCCACUCCUC